AAACUCCUCUUUGAUUCUUCUAGCUGUUUCACUAUUGGGCAACCAGGAAAUGGCCCAAUGGCACUAAAAUCCUGCAGACAACCCUCAGCACAAAACUGUACUUCAGCUUUUUGGUAAGUUUAUUUUCUUCCCAAUUUAUAAGACACCAGAAUGAGUACUAAAAAGUCUCCUGAGGAACUGAAGAGGAUUUUUGAAAAAUAUGCAGCCAAAGAAGGUGAUCCAGACCAGUUGUCAAAGGAUGAACUGAAGCUAUUGAUUCAGGCUGAAUUCCCCAGUUUACUCAAAGGUCCAAACACCCUAGAUGAUCUCUUUCAAGAACUGGACAAGAAUGGAGAUGGAGAAGUUAGUUUUGAAGAAUUCCAAGUAUUAGUAAAAAAGAUAUCCCAGUGAAGGAGAAAACAAAAUAGAACCCUGAGCACUGGAGGAAGAGCGCCUGUGCUGUGGUCUUAUCCUAUGUGGAAUCCCCCAAAGUCUCUGGUUUAAUUCUUUGCAAUUAUAAUAACCUGGCUGUGAGGUUCAGUUAUUAUUAAUAAAGAAAUUAUUAGACAUAC